GAAACAGAGGCUGAACGCGUCAAGUAUUUCACAGCCAGCAGGAAAUCAGAACUUGAACCCAGGCAGUCUAGCCCUGGGAUCCUUUCCCCUUACCCAUUAUCCAGUGUUGGCUACACAAAACUAAUGAGUACAUAUUUUCAACUAUAGUUUAAGUGGGUGACAUAUUUUUCACUAUAUUUUAUGUAGGUGACUUUCAGUUUGGGGGUAUUCUACUUACACAAUCUAUUGAGCUGGAUAUUAACUGAGAGCAAACAGAAACUAAUGAACUCUGAAAAACAUAAAACAUGAGCAACAUGACAUCACUGCAAGAGACAAAACAGCACAUAGCCUUCUUGUGACUGUAUUUUGCUGACAGUCCAUGAGAUGAUAGCCUGAACUCAGCAGUGCUGUUCCCUUGGGAGACACACACACACACACACACACACACACACACACACACACACACACACACGAGUUGGUGGUUGUGCUGCCCGGAGCCUCCAGUCCGCGAGUGUGAAGAACGGACCAGAUGGGUCCAGCAGUGCUGGGUCAAGGCGAGGAGGGGGCAGCCGGAAGCGCGCGCAUGCUCUGGACUCCUGCAGCCGCCAAAACGGUCAGGUUUUCCUUGUUCCCGCAUGUUCAGCCAAUCGUGUUUAAGGAGAAACUAACAAUGAAAACGGACUCGUUGAUGGAGGAAAAGUUGGAAUGCAGCCUCUGGUGCUGUUUGAGCGAUCCCUCUACCCCGGGUCGCUGCUGUGUUCUGGAAAGGCGCAUUGUACCCUGGAUGCAGCAGAAGAUCGUUCUGAAAGAUAAUGCCAACUCGGAACCUAGGAAACCAUCCAGUGGGUUUCUGCAGCUUAGGUGUUUCAAAUCCUCAUCAGCACGUUUGUUUUCUCUGCCUCAGUUUGCUUACAAUGAUGUUCUCAGUAGCUACAAUUGCUGUCUUUGAAUACGUAAGCAUUUUUUUUUAGGUGACAGGGAUAUAUGUGCAUUUUUAUUUUACCAAGUGUUAGAAUUUUGACUCUGCUUUUGUGGGCUCUGGGUUAGCUACUUGGUUGUUGUAAAAUGAUUAGCAGGGAAAGCUGUGUGUGUGUGUGUGUAUGUGUGUGUGUUAUAAGUUUCUUUUGUUGUCAGAGGACUUAGAAUUUUAUUUUAUAUGGUAAUUCUGUCAAUUUACUUUAUUCUCCACCCCACAUUUAUUGAACAGCAAAUUAUGAAAGUAAUGUGUCCCAUAAGCAGCCUUCAGAAGAAUUACAACUGCUGUAUAUCUGAAAUUCUUUUUUUUAUUUUUUAUUUUGAGAUGGAGUCUCACUCUAUCACCCAAGCUGGAGUACAGUGGUGC